CCUUCCCCCUCGCCCGCCCGCUCCCGCUUCCAGCGGCGCCGGGCCUCCCGCUCCGCCUCCCCGUGCGCGGCUCUCCCGGGCGCGGCUCCGGGGUUCAUGGUGACGAGGCGGCGGCCGCUCGAGCCCAGCGGCGGCGGCGGCGGGAGCUGGGGCGCGGGCCCGGGCCGCCUCUCCCAGAGCGCGGGGCCGGGCGGCGGGCGCGCCCAGGCAGCGGCUGCGAGCGCCCCCCCGCGCCGCGCCCCCGCGCCCCCCGCGCCGCGCCCCCGCGCGCUUGGCUUGCGGGGGGCCGGGCCUGCGGGCGGCCGCCGCGCCGCGCACCCAUGGACGGCCCGGCCAUCAUCACCCAGGUGACCAACCCCAAGGAGGACGAGGGCCGGUUGCCGGGCGCGGGCGAGAAAG